AGUCUGCACGCCGAGGUCCGCGCUGUGUCCCGUGUUUUCUGCGUGAGGUGAGAGCUGGCUGGCGGGCCAAUGAAGUUCUUGCGGGGAGAGGGGAGUCGGACUAGCCAGGGAGCCAGAUGGAAGAGCCAGGGAGCCAGACAGACUAGCGGGAAAGCCUAAUUGUCGCAGGAAGGGGGUCAGGAGGUUGGGGGGUCGACCUGACCCGGCCUGGAGAGGCGGGGAGGUGGGCGCGUGUCCCGGUUGCUUAGGUUUUGGGAUGCCUCUUACUCUGCCAAGCCGCUUAGCGGGAGGGAACGUGUUCCUGAUCAUCUUUACCCCAGGCUUCUGUCCGGGGCGUGUCAAUGUAGAAAUCCCCCAGCGAAUGUUGGAUGAAUGAAUGAAGUUGAAGAGAGGGUAGGCGGGGAACGAGGAUGAGGGGGACGGCUGGAGAAGAGGUAUGGGAGGUUCGAUGUUUCAGGGAUGGCACCCAAGGGGGACAUCGAGGCAGCACGGUAGCACUUCCUUUGCGAUGAGGGGCGUCUCUUUGGACUUCUUGGAAAAGAGAAGCCCUAGGAUGGAGUCUUGGAUACUUAAUGGCCGGGGUAGAAGAUAAACCUGCAAAGAAAAUCCAGGAGGAGUGCCCAGAAAGGGAGGAAAGCCUCAGCCUCCUGAGUAGCUGGGACUACAGAGGAAAAGAUGCUAGAACCACAGGAGAAUGGCGUGAUUGACCUACCAGAUUAUGAGCAUGUAGAAGAUGAAACUUUUCCUCCUUUCCCACCUCCAGCCUCUCCAGAGAGACAAGAUGGUGAAGGAACUGAGCCUGAUGAAGAGUCAGGAAAUGGAGCACCUGUUCGUGUACCUCCAAAGAGAACAGUUAAAAGAAAUAUACCCAAGCUGGAUGCUCAGAGAUUAAUUUCAGAGAGAGGACUUCCAGCCUUAAGGCAUGUAUUUGAUAAGGCAAAAUUCAAAGGUAAAGGUCAUGAGGCUGAAGACUUGAAGAUGCUAAUCAGACACAUGGAGCACUGGGCACAUAGGCUAUUCCCUAAACUGCAGUUUGAGGAUUUUAUUGACAGAGUUGAAUACCUGGGAAGUAAAAAGGAAGUUCAGACCUGUUUAAAACGAAUUCGACUUGAUCUCCCUAUUUUACAUGAAGAUUUUGUUAGCAAUAAUGAUGAAGUUGCGGAGAAUAAUGAACAUGAUGUCACUUCUACUGAAUUAGAUCCCUUUCUGACAAACUUAUCUGAAAGUGAGAUGUUUGCUUCUGAGUUAAGUAGAAGCCUAACAGAAGAGCAACAACAAAGAAUUGAGAGAAAUAAACAACUGGCCUUGGAAAGAAGGCAGGCAAAGCUGCUGAGUAAUAGUCAGACCCUAGGAAAUGAUAUGUUAAUGAAUACACCCAGGGCACACACGGUUGAAGAGGUUAAUACUGAUGAGGAUCAAAAGGAGGAGUCAAAUGGAUUAAACGAAGACAUUCUGGACAAUCCAUGUAAUGAUGCUAUUGCCAAUACUUUAAAUGAAGAGGAAACACUGCUGGACCAGUCUUUUAAAAAUGUGCAACAGCAACUUGAUGCUACAUCCAGAAAUAUUACUGAAGCUAGAUAAGUUUCCAUUAAGAGAAAAUGUAUCUGUUAAGUCAUCGUCCUGCAAGCUUGGCGUUACUAUGUAUUUUUUCUUCUUGGAGUGAAAAUCCUUAGAUAGUAAAACUGUUAUAGAUUAUUGUUUAAAAUCUGAUAAUCUGGUAUUUAUUUAUAAUUAUGCUUGUCACUUUAGUUAAAUCUAUUUGUUCUCUUUAGUGUUUGUUUUUAUAUAGGUAUUUCUUCAUAAAAUGAUUAGGAGGUAAUAAGCAGUUUCUGCUGCUGGUCUGUCAUUGAAUGCCUUGUUUUCACUAAGUUGGGAGGUUUUGUUUCUGUUUUUUACUGCUCCUUGCAAAGCAGGGCUAAUCCAUGGACAGUGUGCCCAGAGUAGUCUAGUUGAAGUUUUUUGUUUUGUUUUGUUUUGUUUUUUUUGACACAGAGUCUCACUCUGUUGGCCAGGCUGGAGUGCAGUGGCACAGUCUUGGCUCACUGCAACCUCUGCCUCCUGGGCUCAAGCAAUUCUCCUGCCUUAGCCUCCCGAGUAGCUGGGACUACAGGCGUGUGCCACCACGCUUGGCUAAUUUUUGUACUUUUAGUAGAGAUGAGGUUUCACCAUGUUGGCCAGGCUGGUCUCAAACUCCUAACCUCAGGUAAUCCGCCCCCCUCGGCCUCCCAAAGUGCUGGGAUUACAGGUGUGAGCCACCGCGCCCAGCCUGGGUGAAGUUUUGAGAUGUACAUAUAUACUGAAUAUUAAUGUCAAUUUUUUAAAAGAAGUAAAAAUUAUCUUAAAAACUA